CUUCUGCCGAAGAAGUAGGGGCGGGGGGAAGUUUAGGAGUUGAGGAAAGAAGAUUAAAGAGCGCGAGGAGGCACUGCCAGGACUUACCGUACAACACUCCUUGGCUUCUGGAAUUUUAUCUCUGCUCACAGUCUACAUUACAACAUUAGUUCAUUCUGGGCACUUUAGCUUCCUUGAAUCUCCAGUUGAUCUCACACCCAUGCCUAUGAUAUUCUUCUCCUGGUUAAUCAAGAAUUCUCUAUUUCUGCUCCGUCAUCCAUGCCACUACAAAUAAAAAGAAGUGUUAAGAAUUGCCUUUGGGACUCUGAAGGCUGAAGAAUUGAUGAAUUGCAAGUUUGUGCCCCAUAGCUGCACAGACUGCCUGAAGUUACAUUUAGAGACUGAAAUCACUGCACCUUAAAAACAAAAGAUUGAGCUGCACUGUAUUCCUAAUGUUUCAUCAUUACUAACAGGAUAUUCCUCAUGACAUUGCUGUCUGAGGUGAAACCCGCCAGCCAAUAGCAGUACUGAUACCAAAUCACCUGUUGAUUCUGUUAAUUCAUAUCUUUGACCAUCAGUCUGUGACCUGCCCCUUCUCUUUACAUGCAGCCGCUCUCUGCUCCCUGCCCCAAUGAACAUCUGCACUAGGCCCAAGCCUUGGAGUAAUUUACCUGAAGAGUGACACCAUUGAUUUUGAAACUACUACUUCUAUGUUACUGGAAAACGCUAAACCUGGGAGACUAACAUCCCUCUUAGGCUUCAGAUGAGGAAACUGAAGCCCAGAGAGGUGAAGUGAGGUGCCCAAGGCCACACAGCAAGUUAGAGGCACAGCUAGUACGGUAGCUCAAGUCUCCUGACUCCCAGUCCAGUGCUCCUCCCAUUACUCCACGAGUCCUGUCUCUAAGCUUCCUGACAAAUGCUAGAACGGAAGAAACCCAAGACAGCUGAAAACCAGAAGGCAUCUGAGGAGAAUGAGAUUACUCAGCCGGGUGGAUCCAGCGCCAAGCCGGGCCUUCCCUGCCUGAACUUUGAAGCUGUUUUGUCUCCAGACCCAGCCCUCAUCCACUCAACACAUUCACUGACAAACUCUCACGCUCACACCGGGUCAUCUGAUUGUGACAUCAGUUGCAAGGGGAUGACCGAGCGCAUUCACAGCAUCAACCUUCACAACUUCAGCAAUUCCGUGCUCGAGACCCUCAACGAGCAGCGCAACCGUGGCCACUUCUGUGACGUAACGGUGCGCAUCCACGGGAGCAUGCUGCGCGCACACCGCUGCGUGCUGGCAGCCGGCAGCCCCUUCUUCCAGGACAAACUGCUGCUUGGCUACAGCGACAUCGAGAUCCCGUCGGUGGUGUCAGUGCAGUCAGUGCAAAAGCUCAUUGACUUCAUGUACAGCGGCGUGCUACGGGUCUCGCAGUCGGAAGCUCUGCAGAUCCUCACGGCCGCCAGCAUCCUGCAGAUCAAAACAGUCAUCGACGAGUGCACGCGCAUCGUGUCACAGAACGUGGGCGAUGUGUUCCCGGGGAUCCAGGACUCGGGCCAGGACACGCCGCGGGGCACUCCCGAGUCAGGCACGUCAGGCCAGAGCAGCGACACGGAGUCGGGCUACCUGCAGAGCCACCCACAGCACAGCGUGGACAGGAUCUACUCGGCACUCUACGCGUGCUCCAUGCAGAAUGGCAGCGGCGAGCGCUCUUUUUACAGCGGCGCAGUGGUCAGCCACCACGAGACUGCGCUCGGCCUGCCCCGCGACCACCACAUGGAAGACCCCAGCUGGAUCACACGCAUCCAUGAGCGCUCGCAGCAGAUGGAGCGCUACCUGUCCACCACCCCCGAGACCACGCACUGCCGCAAGCAGCCCCGGCCUGUGCGCAUCCAGACCCUAGUGGGCAACAUCCACAUCAAGCAGGAGAUGGAGGACGAUUACGACUACUACGGGCAGCAAAGGGUGCAGAUCCUGGAACGCAACGAAUCCGAGGAGUGCACGGAAGACACAGACCAGGCCGAGGGCACCGAGAGUGAGCCCAAAGGUGAAAGCUUCGACUCGGGCGUCAGCUCCUCCAUAGGCACCGAGCCUGACUCGGUGGAGCAGCAGUUUGGGCCUGGGGCGGCGCGGGACAGCCAGGCUGAACCCACCCAACCCGAGCAGGCUGCAGAAGCCCCCGCUGAGGGUGGUCCGCAGACAAACCAGCUAGAAACAGGUGCUUCCUCUCCGGAGAGAAGCAAUGAAGUGGAGAUGGACAGCACUGUUAUCACUGUCAGCAACAGCUCCGACAAGAGCGUCCUACAACAGCCUUCGGUCAACACGUCCAUCGGGCAGCCAUUGCCAAGUACCCAGCUCUACUUACGCCAGACAGAAACCCUCACCAGCAACCUGAGGAUGCCUCUGACCUUGACCAGCAACACGCAGGUCAUUGGCACAGCUGGCAACACCUACCUGCCAGCCCUCUUCACUACCCAGCCCGCGGGCAGUGGCCCCAAGCCUUUCCUCUUCAGCCUGCCACAGCCCCUGGCAGGCCAGCAGACCCAGUUUGUGACAGUGUCCCAGCCCGGUCUGUCGACCUUUACUGCACAGCUGCCAGCGCCACAGCCCCUGGCCUCAUCCGCAGGCCACAGCACAGCCAGUGGGCAAGGCGAAAAAAAGCCUUAUGAGUGCACUCUCUGCAACAAGACUUUCACCGCCAAACAGAACUACGUCAAGCACAUGUUCGUACACACAGGUGAGAAGCCCCACCAAUGCAGCAUCUGUUGGCGCUCCUUCUCCUUAAAGGAUUACCUUAUCAAGCACAUGGUGACACACACAGGAGUGAGGGCAUACCAGUGUAGUAUCUGCAACAAGCGCUUCACCCAGAAGAGCUCCCUCAACGUGCACAUGCGCCUCCACCGGGGAGAGAAGUCCUACGAGUGCUACAUCUGCAAAAAGAAGUUCUCUCACAAGACCCUCCUGGAGCGACACGUGGCCCUGCACAGUGCCAGCAAUGGGACCCCCCCUGCAGGCACACCCCCAGGUGCCCGCGCUGGCCCCCCAGGCGUGGUGGCCUGCACGGAGGGGACCACUUACGUCUGCUCCGUCUGCCCAGCAAAGUUUGACCAAAUCGAGCAGUUCAACGACCACAUGAGGAUGCAUGUGUCUGACGGAUAAGUAGUAUCUUUCUCUCUUUCUUAUGAACAAAACAAAACAACAACAAAAAACAAACAAACAAAAAAGCUAUGGCACUAGAAUUUAAGAAAUGUUUUGGUUUCAUUUUUACUUUCUGUUUUUGUUUUUGUUUCGUUUCAUUUUGUACUACAUGAAGAACUGUUUUUUGCCUGCUGGUACAUUACAUUUCCGGAGGCUUGGGUGAAUAAUAGUUUUCCCAGUCUCCCUCGGAUGGUGGCCUUAAGGCCUGGUAGUGCUUCAAGAGGUCCACUGGUUGGAUCUCUAGCUACUGGCCUCUAAAUACAACCCUUCUUUACAAAAAAAUCUUUUAAAAAAAAGUAAAAAAAAAAAAAAAAUUUCCACUUGUGAAGAGCACUACAAAAAAUAUAUAACAAAAUCUAAAAGGCCUACUGUCUUUAAGUACACCGCUUGCAGUGUUUCAGUGGACAUUUUCACAAUUCUGGCCGCUUGGACUUCACAGUAACCAGUUAAAACUGUGGAAUAUCACUUCUGGUUGAAAACCCAGAGGAAAGGCCCUGCUGUUUUCCACCUACCACGUUGUCUGAUUUCAUAAAAGGGCUGUGGGGGUGGGAAGGGCAGUGGGUUCGGUGGUGUGGGAAAGAAAGACGAAUGGCAGGCUUCUUCCCCAGAUUCUGCCCGGGUCCACACACCCUGGCCCACCUUCUCCAUAUCCCCCUCUUGCAGCAGAAGCCAGGAAGACUUGGACAAGCAACAAGCAACAGUGGCUAUCGUAUUUAUUCAGUGUCUUCGCUGAGCCACAGCCUCAGCACAAUCAAGAGGGACUUUCAUGAAAGGCAGGAAUGCAGAUAAAACAAAGAUAUCAGAAAUUUGCACCUAUGUUUCUAGGUACAAGAGAAGGAUUAUUUCCAACAAUCUUUGCAAAAAAAAAAAAAGUGUCAGGAUAUAUUCUUGUGGAAGAGAAAAAGAAAAAGAAAUGGAGGGUGGGGGGAACAAUAAAAAGUUCUUGAGGCUUUUUUAAUUCAAAAUUUUAUAGAGGGGCAAAAGUGACGUUUACCAGAUAGAAUGCUGAUUUUUUUAAUAUAUUUACAACAGUAUUUGUGUAAAAAAAAAAACAAAAAAAGUGAAAUUGUUAAAAGUAAUUUUUUUCAUUUUGGUUUUGCAUACACUGCCACCAAUUCCUUCUCUUUUAUUUUAUUUCACACACAUAUAUAUAUUUUUUGGUAAGUCAAGACUGUUAAGGUUAGCGAUACUGCUUCCAGAUAGAAAGAAUAAAAGGCAACUAAAGUUAUAUUUGAAAGAGAGGAAGGAUAUUUUCUUCAUAUUUUUUUUAAUUUUUCUUAAUUUUUAUUAUUUUAAGUAUUGCCUGGGUUGAUGAGGGCCUCUGUGGCCAGCCCAUCCCUGCUGUAAUUUGAAUUGCUGCUUUGUAUUUUGAUAUGUAGUUCUUUGACUUUAGCAAGCUUAAGUUGCCCCACUGAAUAAUUUUUUCAACUGAUUCAUCUAGAAUUCUGUUCUUUUUCAUGGAAGAGACUUUAUCUUUCAGAAAGAGAUUGCUUGCUUCUCCAAAAUUUCAUUGAGAUCUUACAAUUCUAGAAUUUCUAUUGACUUUACUUUUUUUCUUAGUGAAACACUAAUAGUCUAGAAGUCUUGAUAAAUGGGGUCUUUUCUUUUGUGAUCAGCCAGGAAGAGGAGUUCACAAAACUCUGCCAUAGCUCCUCACCCUUCCCAACUACAAAGAGCAUCAUUAUGAGAAGCCUGUUAUAGAUCAAGAUGCAUUGAUGCCAAAAUUACUUUUUUCCUUCCAAAUAUCACCUUCUGACUGUUUCCACCAUGGUUAAGAGGGCUGAAUAAGAUGAUCAUUCUUUAGAUGACGAAUUAACCCUUGCUUCUUCGAAAGGUUUUAGGGAAAUUAACAAAAAAAUUCCCAGAUGCCAACAGCCACCAUUCAAAAGACCACCAAUCUAUUGCAUCAUACCAGAUGCCACUCUCUCUUCCUAGUAGGGAUUUCUCUCCUCGGUCCUGAUCAAGGUGUUAUAAUAGAGACAUUUUCAUUAUAGACAGUGUCCUGAAGGGAUUCCAGCUCAAAUAUAGGAAUUCUUAAACCUAGCUGAAACUCCCAAAGUGAUUUCAUUGCUGGGCAUAUUUUAACAUACUUAGGGGAAAGCAAAUCUUUAAACAAAGCAAAACACCAAACUACAGUUUUAAAAAGAAGAAAGGAGAGCGUAUUUUAGUUUCAAAAUUACAUUACAUUUUAAUUUAAUUUUCCUUCUAAUUUUCCUGUCAGCAUUUUAUUUACAAAAACUGUGCAGCAAACGAGGGAAAAUCUUCCAACACAAACAACUCUGUAAUGACUAAAUUGGUUUUAUUCAUAUAUUUUAGACAUUUGGUUAACUUGGAUCUUUUUCAUAAGUUCUUUGUGAUGCUUUGUAAGGUUAGUGUAACUGAAGUGUUUGUGAGUUUGAUUUGGUCCCACAGUGCUUAAUUCAGUGGAUAUUUUGCUAGAAGUUUUAAUGUAAACUUGGGUGGUUAACUGACUAUUAAGUGUAACCUAUUGUGAUUUCUAAGAGGAGUCCUGCCAAGAACUGUAUGUCCAAAACUGAUCUGUUUUAACAGUUAGUGAGGAACAGCUUCCGAGAUAAAGUAAGUUCAUUUUUCUAUUGCUAAUUUUGCUUUUUAAAAUAGCAGUGUUGUAAGACUAAUAUUUCCACUUACCACCAAUAGAGGGAGCAUUAAUUAACUAUGUCAUGGAAUUGUUUUGAUAUUUUGGAAAACAAGUGAUUCCACCCAUAAAAUGAAAAGAGAAGAUUGACCUUAAGAAAAAAACUCUUAAAGCUAGGAGACAAUGACAUGAAAUCACUCAAUACAUGUUACAAAUGAAAGAAGGCCAAAAGCCACUUUAAAAUAUUUUAAACUGUUUCACAGUAGAUUUGAAAGUGUCUUUGUUCAAAUUUAGCAAAGUAGGAAGAAUUUUCACUAAUACCGCCUGAAAAGUUGAUCUUAGGUGCCAUUAUGGGCCACGUGUAGCUUUCUGUUUCUCAAAUCUGAGAGAGACCCAUUUGCCUUAAUGCUGAUUUGCCAUGUAAAAUGCUAAGCAAUUGGGUUAGAAUCCACCUUUUCUUUUGGUAGAACAUGUAGAGAAAAAGCUGCAGGUGACUUGAAACCCUGAGGAGUCUAUCAUCCUUUCCCUGUAAAGGAAGUGUCUCUUAAAAAAAAGGGAGUGGGGGAGGAGGUGGAGGAUCCCUAAAGAAUUCUUAAUGAGGUGAUAUAAUCAUUGUAGUCCAUGACAAAAUGGACCAGCCAGGUUUGCAUAGCAGUAGACAUAUUCCUACUGUACAUUUAUCCUUCCCAAAUAUGUCACAUUCUAAAAUAGUUGACAAAUUAUUUUGUGGAAAGAGGAAGAAGCUGGAUUGGAGUGGGAGAUCUAAUCUGGAGGAGCAAAGAGGUAGUUGUUUAUUGCUAUGUUCCUGGCCCAUCAAAUGGCCACUUUCCAAACUGACCCACAUUUUAGGAAAUAAACCAAUCUGGACCUGUUUCAAAAGGAUAGAGAUGCUUUUAGAUUGUCAAUUCUCACUUUUAAGUUAAACAAUCACAAAUAUCUUUAGAAAUAGGGAAAGACAUUUGCUUCAAAAUCAAAGAAUGAGUGUGGAUCUUUUUAAUUUUUUUUUGUUUCAAGUCCUACAGUCAUCUUACAUUUAGACCUUCAUGGUAGGGUGAUAUGAGUGCUAAAAAAAUUUCUUUCUAGUAGCCAGGAAACAGAUAGAUAAGAUAAAAGCAAAUGUUCCAGAUUUAAGACUUCUUAGGAUGAGUACAAGGAAGAGAGAAAUAGUAUGGAAAGGACAUUUUUUAGCAAUUUAUAAUUUUAAAAUGGAAUUUGCCAAACAAGGGAGAGGAAAAAAAGUCAAAGGGGAAUUUUUAUCUCAAGAUAUUUAGAUAUGGUUUAUAAAAAAAUAAUAUUUUCUACCACUAAAAACACUGGUAUUAUCUCAGCAUCAUGGGCAAUUUUUCCUUAUUACAUGCCAAUAUUUGUACAAAAAAGGCCCCCAAAUGUGUGAAAUAUAAUCCUAAAAAAGAAAAUAAUUGGAACACAUGGAUCUGUUACAAUUCUACACAGGGGGAAACAAGCUAAGCAAAGAAAAAAAAUCUGAAAUGAAAAUCUCUGUAUCAAAAUGGUUUCCUGUAUCUUUUAAUUGAGAGGUAAACUUUAGCUCCUAAUAACAGUUUUAUAGACCGUUCUCUUCCCAAAUUCCUAAUGCUUUGAAUCUAUUUGUGCCAUGAUUAAGUGUGCUGGAUAAUUUCCUGCUCAUAUUCUAGCCUCAGUUCAUUCCUAGUCAUCUUAGAGAUCAUAGUAGCUCUUGGCCUUAGAAAGACUUGGGUUUGCUGUGUUUAAAAGUCAUAAGGGUUUUAUUUUGUAUCAUCAAAAUAUUCUAUAAGGUCCCAAAUACUCUUUUUCAACCCAUGAACAGUAAGAAUUUGUGAAUUCUGAUAAUGAAAAAAGUUUUCCUCCAGGUAUGUUUGUUUCACAUUCAGUCCUAAAGCCUUGAGCUAUGUGUACUUCCCUCACACAGGAACACCAGCUGUCCUGUCUGUGCUCUGCCUGCGCCCAAAACUCAAUAUUUUCUCUCAGCACAGAAGUCAAAAAUGAGAUAUGCCCCUUAUAAAACCCCUUCGAUUCCUGAGAAAACAUAAUAAAGCCAUAUGUUGCUUCCUUGUUGGGGCUCCUCCACAAUGCUCCCAACACCUGUGACCCCUAGGAAGACAGGGAGCAAGGUGGAUCUGGCCAGGAGUCACAGGAUAUACACCCAUUCUGGAGCUUUCCUCUGUUGUUCUAGAAGAUGUUAUUUGAUUAGUUGGGGCUGGGAGCAGGGGAUAUAUGAUUUUGUGGAAAAGGUAUCAGAUAAUCAAAUCAGGUCUGCCUCUGCUAUAGCCAGUGUGCUGCUGCAUUAAAAGGGAACAAAAGGAAGGUGCAACGUAAGAGCAGACACAACCUGAGAUGCCCUUGAGAUUUAGGAGAACAGGAGGGCGCCCUUUCUGUUGUGACCUGACUCUUAAAAGAAAUCUUCUAAAAGAAUUCUUUAAUUUGGUAAUGAGUUGAAGUCCAGGGUAAUGGAAGCUCUAGGGCAGAGAACAAAAGAAUUGCAAAAUGUAUUCAGCACCAAACAAUGCUAAACCAAGAAACAUCCAAUCACAAAACUAGGAAGUUUGGCAAGAAGUGGUUAGAGAAAUCUCUGGGCUUUUCCAUGGGCAGGGUCGACAGACUCUCUUUUCAGUGAUUUCUGGCUCUGAGAAACCUCUUUACUCACUAGAAAAGAACUUUAUUUAAAUGGCCAAUUUUGUUCCUCAGAAAAAGAAAUUAAAAAAAAAGAAAAAUAGGAUACUGAAGACAGAACCAUGUGACUUGGUGACAAACAAAAGGAGGGGUGCACUAGAAUUUCAAUAGGCUCCCUAAUUCCAUAGAAAAAGCAAAGCAACCCAAUGCCUCCUGAGCCUGCAGUGCAUGAAGAGAGUGCUUGAGCUGACCCAGCCACCAGGCCUUCUGGGGCUAGACAUAACUUCCCACUGGAACAGCAGCAGCCUCUUUCCCCUCUUUGUGUUUUCAUGAAGAAAACGGCUGUUCUCUUAGGUAGCCAGGAAAUAGAUUACAUGGGGCAAACUUUCAAAAGCAAUCUCUACCCUGGUGCUCAGGCUACAUACAGAGGCAGAAAAGGGGCACGGAAGAGCCCUUGCUCUUGAGAGAGAGUAUUUUCAUAUUCCCAAGGGCUUUCCGUGUAGAGUUGCUAUUUCUGAUAUCACUUAAACCUUUACAAGAAAAAAGGCUGUGGUGACUCAGUGUUCCUAUAAAUUCAGAAUGUGGAAACUACUAAUCCAAAGCAUCAUUUCUAGCACUGAGUAUCAAGACGAUCAGCCUGACCAAAAUAUUGCAAAGAGUUUUCUAAGUCUCUGAAGAUUUUUUUCUCCUUGAACACUGAGUCUAUAGCAGUCAGCAAUGUACCUUAGCCGAUCCCUGGGAAUGGUUAUGGAACAGUAGGGCUUGUUUCCAUCCUUUUUAGAGUGAAGAGAUAGAAAAUUAGGGCUACCUAGUGUGGGUUCUUUUUCAGAACUAUGUAUUUUCUCCUCACUGCAUGAUGGGUAAAAAUGCCCUGGGUUGAAACAAGAAACAUUAUCUUUCCACACCACUGACUAAAACACCUGCCAGUGGUUUCUUUAGGCUCCACCUUUUGCUCCGUAAACUGUAGACUUUCAGACUGAAAUCUAAUCUUAAGUGACCUCAAUUAAGGUAUUUUCACAAAAGGCUACUUAUAGUGUAGCAUUAUUGCCUUAAAUCAGAAAGCCCUGGGAAGAGGAUAAAAGAUAUAGAAAUGAGAAGGCUCUGAAGUUAUAGGCAUUUCUUGCUGUUUAAUAGUUACAUUAUCACAAAAACAAGCCCUAUUCAUGAUUGAGGACUAUGGAAAUAGUGACUUCUUGAGGAGGCACCAAACUUUCCUAGAACUGGGUACUCUCAGAUAGUGGCUGCUAUUUCCUAUUCUAUUUCAGUGACGUAGGUUGGGGCUGAAUGUAAAAUAGACAUCAUAUUACUAAAUAGAAUCCUAUAAAAUGCAAUCACAGGUGCCCGGGAGUACUAGUUUUAAACAUUUCCUUAACAAGGAGAACAAUCCAGCAAAAAGCUUUCUUUCUCUAUACAGUGUAUAUCUCUAAACUUUUUUUCCUCAGUUUUAGAGAACAUCUGUUUUAUCUGGUGGUUCUUUGUUUGAAUGCAAACUCAUAACUUUCAAGUCUCCGGUGCAAGAGCAUAAUCUACAGAUCAUGGGCAAAAUCUAGCCACAGUCCUGAGAGUCCAGGCUUCUGGGAUGCCCAGCUGGGUAUAAAAGUCCCUACUAACCCUGUUUCAAAUUCAGAGGUUUCUUUGGUUUAGAAUGCCUCAAUGAGAUUUUGAUACAUCCAAGAGAGAAAAAAAAAAAAAAAAAAAAAAAAACCUUGGGGGCAUCUGUUUCUACUAGUGUUGCAACAGUUGUUUUUACCCAGCAAACUCAUUGCAAUUUAUAUGUAGAUUCUAAUAAUGAAAGAGUCUUAACCCAUCCAGUAUGUCACCGCUGCUGUCCAAAAUGUCUAUAAAUGAGUAUACAUUAUUUAUACAUGUGCACACACAGUGUGAGCUUCCCUCAGCACAAAACUGUUUCACAUUCAUAUUGCCCAGUGACAACAAGAUACAUUUUUGAACUUCUGGUUAGAAGUCGAAGGUCUGACAUAUCUCACGUAUCUGCUUAUGCUUUGUUGCCUUAGUUGGGUGCAUCAGUAUCUGUGAUGAGACUUUAGGGCAUUCUGAAGGAGCCCAACCAUCAGUAAUUUCUAUGUAUCCGUUUCAUGAGAAACUUGAAUAUGCUUAUGUGGAGUAGAGUGCAUUUAACAAACUCUACAGUUCUAUUGGAUUUAUUGACAUGUGUGCACAUGUGUGUGUUUGUGUAUAUACUUAUUGUCAUCUGGAAGUGUGUGUGCCCCCCAAAGGAAGCACACACAGGCAGAGGUCCUCGUGCAUAGAUACAGUUGCCUCUUCCCACCAUUGUGUUUAAGACUUGUGGCUCCCUUCCCAGGAAGCAGUCACCUGCCCACUCUGUUGCUUUUUGUAAUGUUUCAGAAUUGGGAGAAACAAAUGCAGCUUGUUGAAUCCACAGCAAACCCACAGGGACAGGCUGUUUUCCUCCAUAAUAAGGUAUAACAGAAGUCUUCAACUGGUGAGCAGACAAGAGGGAGCAGCAGUCCAGGGCGUCUCCCCAGGUCUCCUGGAGGUGGCAGGGGUGGGGACCAAUGCCAGGCAGGCAAAGCCCACACAAACUUUGGCCUGAGCCAUCCCAUAGCUCAAAGGUCUUCAUUCCUUUCCUCUAUGCAAUGCAGUGUGCACACACACACACACACACACACACACACACAUAAAUUUUAUUCUCAAACUAAAGCUUCCUAAUUCUGCCUGUACUCACAAGAUAUCAUCGUAAUUCACAAACUGUGUCUCCUGAAACCAAUGUGGCCUUUGCCAAAGUCUUUCCAGGAGUGGGUUGUUUACCAUGUCUAGCAAACCAAUAGACUGUUGGGGGGAAUGUUUUUUGGUAAUCUGUAGGAAUUGAUUGCUCUUGCCCAUCUCAAGCAUUGAAGUAGAAUGCCACUCUAGUAUAAUAUACUGAAUGAAUGGACUCUGAGGGUUUGGUGGCCUGGAAUUCAGGAUUCAGUUUUCUCACUCCCAUGCCCUUCUUUUACUAGAUGGUUUGUUAUUUUUUAUGAUUUGUACAUUAUUUCUGUUUUACAGAAGUCAGAGGACAUUUUCUUUCCUCUUCUAUUCUGGUGACUUUUCCCCUUCCCCUGUUAAGUAAGGCUACUUACAGUUGCAACUUUUUUGUCGUUAUUACUUUUUAAAAUGUAUAUUGUCUUUCUAUAUCCAAAAGAAGUCUGUAACUGUAACCAUAGGUAUUUCUUUUUACUGGAAAAACAAUUAGUUGUUUCGGUUUUAUUUUUUCCUUUAAUUAACAGUACUAGUGACUUUGUGAAAGAAUAUGAGUUACUAUUUAGGUAUGCUUACUUAACUACAAUACACUACAUUGCAGUAUUUCUGAAACCUAGGACAUACACAUUAUAUAUAACAACUCUAUAUUGAAAUAUAUAUUACAUUAUAUUCAUUUUAACUUUUGAAUCUGCCUAUGAUCAUGAGUUGAUUGAAAUAUUAUGUCUUUGCUUAUAUCACCCAUCACCAACCUGCUGCAGUUAAUCUGGUGCAUCUAGUAAUAAUCAUUAGUGCUCUAAUUUGCUUUUUAUAUUAUCAGCUUCAGUAUUGUCUUUAGAGGAUUUUAGAAUUUUUUAAAGCUCAGACUUAGCAAAUGUAGGAAAGUGAAAACUUUUUUUGAAACUUUUUUGUUGGUGUGACUAAUACAAAGAGGUUCAUAUUCAAAGUGAUCUUGUUUAGCUGACCCACUCAAUAUCUGAAGAACAAAAGAGGUGCAUAUGAAUGUAUCUGUGAUUUUCCCCUGUAGGACUGUCACUGUCUAUAUUUGCUUUUAAAAAUAUGACCAAGGGGCUACUUAAGUGCCACAUGAUCUGACCAACAAUAACAGGCUGCGUUUCAAAGGGCCAGUCUUCUGAAAAGCGUAAGACAGUGAAUUACCUAGUUGUCCCCACUGUAUUCUCAAACAUUCAUUUUAAUACUGGAUCUUUACACUUUCUUUUUUCAAUACGCUUAGAAUUAUUUUAACUAGUCUUCAACCUUUCCCUGGAGGCAGCUUGGCAAUAUAGUGUUCAUUUUCCUGGGAGUUGUUUUUUUUUUUUUUUUUUUUUUUUUUUUCCAAAAAAAGUAAAACCAGAGUUUCAGGAACUCUUUAUCCACAGAGGCUAAUAGAAAUAGAAUUUGGAAAUAUCUAUCUGAGACAUUUUUAAAUCUGAGGAAUCCGUAAAAUGGUGGCUCUUGGGUAUCCAGCCCUCAGGAUCUCCAUUUACCUGUUAAAGUGAGGAUUUGGUGCCUUUCUUCUUUAGUUGGGCCAUCAAGAAAACUUCAGAAAUCAGGCAUUCUGUCUUCCUAUACAAUAAAUAUUUUCAGAUCAUAUUUUCAGAUAAGAGUCUUCAGCUUCCCUCAGCUAUUCAACCCAAUGCAUGGAAAGCCUCAGUUGAAUAAACUUUUCCACCAUCCCAGGUGCCUGAAACUAGUGUCCUUCUUCACUUCUACAUUCAGGACAAAAUGAAGUCAGGUUUUUAAAACCUCAGUAUAAAAGACCCCCUCACACUGGUCCAAUAUGAAGACUUCUCAGCGUGAACACUGGGGAAUUCCUUCCUUUCAUCUUUCCUAAUAGAUUGUUGUUUUCUAAUCCCAUCCCAUUCUGCUGUACCUCUCCAGCAAGUCCCUUUUCACCUUAGCCAAGCUCCCUGCAAUGCUCUUCAGUUGUGAAGCCUUGUAUUCACUAAGGAACUACGUACUCUUAGUCUGCUUUGAAAGGGCUAAUGUCUAGUGUAAUGGCAAAAUUACCAAUCUGUUCUCCAAAGUGUUCCAGCAGAUAUAUUUCUACUAGACAAACAUAAUUGUGAAUUGACUGUUAGUGAGGCUGUUUCUUCUCUAAUGAUCACAUAAUAUCCAAAUUAUAUCAACUUCAUUAUUUCCCUCUUUCCUUUUCCUAACCCUUUCCCUUUAUUUCUUGUUUCUCUUGAAGACUACUUCAAAUUACCUAUUUGUCUUCAUUACUGCCCCCAAAACUCUAAUAAUUGUGACCCCUAACUGUUCAUUUCUCUUCCUUUCUCCACCCCAUUCUGAACAUCCUUCUUUAAGUUUUAUUUAAUGAAAGAACACUAAAGUGAGUGAGUUCAUAAACUUGAGACUCGUAGGCAGAGUGAAGCAUGUCUUCAUUUUAGCUUCAGAGUUUAAAAGUUAUCAAUAUUCUUUUGAGAGUGGGAGGACCUGAGUCACAGUUUUAAAUGUCAACUGUACUAGCUGAGGUCAUUAAUUCCCCUUACCUUCACGUUUGGCCAAAAAUGAAGAGAAAAAUAUUUUCUGUUUUUUUUUUAAAUACCACAGUGUUCAGGUUCUUCAUAUGAGUAAAUCACUUUUGACGGAGAAAAAAAGAAUCAUUAAUGUUGACUGUUUCCACUAGUCAAAUUACUUGUUUAUCAGACUUUAGAUUAUAGGAAUCUAAAGAAAAGAGUAACAUUUCAAAAUAAUUUUGAUAACUGUUCAAGCCUUAGUGAGCUCUUCUCAAACAAGAAAAGCCACAUCCACUUGAACACAUUGUAGGAAAAAUUAGGAAGAGUUUUUUUAUUUAUUGCCUUUUUGAAAAAAAAAUCAUUGAUUUGUUUAGAACUUUGAGCAGUAACUUACUAAUGGAUGAAAAGAUCCAUAAAGUUUUGAAAGUGUCUGUUUUUGCAACCAGAGAUUGCCUAAACAUAAACUUAAUAUAUACUUAAAUAAAAUAAUAACAGAGCUAAAUGGAUACCUAAAGAGCCAUGCAGUGCACUCCCCAGCACCUAAAUACGCCCCAUAUAAUUUGGUUGUCAUGCUAGAUCUCCCUGCAGUGGAUUACAACUGUCUGGUCACCAGAGCAUUGCCCAAAAGACUGACUGAUACCAUUCUGGGUGUAUCCUUUUCAGGAUGCUUAUAAUAUCACAUUCACAACAACUUCGUAACACAGUCUUUCCUGACUUCUGGUCCAAUAUUCUUGCCAUGAUACCACAUCGCCUCUCAGCUUUAAUGAAGACAAGUCCUGUGACAUUUAGAGUACUAUGUGGUUUUGAGUGCAUAGGCGGUAUGCUUUCAGUUCUUGCUUUACCCUUUGACAAAAAGAAUCAACAUUUAAUAUCAGAAAUGUAUUUUUAUUUGACUUGAGAUUUGACCCAGCUUUUAUCUUAAUCAAACCAGUUUAUAACAUCAACUCACACCAUAGAGAACAAUGAAAUAAAUAGCAGUUUUGAAAGCCUUUAUGAGGCAUGCAUCUAGUAGGAAAACAACAUCUCUUAAAGGCAAUAUUUACAUUGCUUAGGACUAUGAUCUUCACUUGGAAUGUUCUCCCAAUCAAUCCUAUAUCCUUCUUUUUCUUUGUCCAUUCUAACUCCUGGUAUUUUUUUUUUCUUAAAGUACUCUUUAUCUAAAGUAAUCCUCUCCUUAGGCACUGGCUUCCAAAGGAAGAAAGACUCUUUUAAAUCCUAAAAUGCUGUCAUUUAAAGUAUAAUAUGGAGGAGGAGAGGCUCUGGUUCUGAUAGAUCUUACUUGGUCCUCAAUCUGGGAUGCCUUCUUGAUGCUGUUCUUUCUAGUUCCCCAAGAAGUAUUCCAACCCCAAGACCCAGAAUUUCUCACCACAACCUCUGUGUUAGUCUCAGAUUAAUGUCUAAAUCCUGUUUGAUAUUCUAGAGACUCCAGGGUGUGAAUUUAUUAUUGCUUAUGAGCCUCCUGUCUUUCCAAGCUGACACCUGUCAGGAGCAUCAAUAGCCCUAACAGUAACUAAUGCAUCAAAAUAAUAGACAGAAACACUAUAGUAUAUAUUCGUGAGGAUAGGAAGAUUUUUUUUUCUUCUUUUCUCCAGGAAAAGCUUGCUUUGCUCCCCUCUCCCUCUGCAACACACACACAUACAAUGCAUUUCAGAAAGUCUGCAUCUUAUUUUACAGAUAUGUAGCUCUAGAAUUUACAAAUAUAGCUUAGGAAAUGUUCUGAGAUUGAGGCUGGUAGCAAACAAGUUUAUUUUCUGCACUGGACUUCAGGAUAAGUGUGCAUAGAUGCAAUUCCUUCAAAGAAAGUGAAACAUGGUAGAGCAAAGGGAUAAUACUUUCACACAUUCAAACAGUUGUUUGCUAUCUAUAAACCUUGAUUUAAGCAUAAUUAUUACUUUUUAGAAAUCUGAAACUGGAGGAAUGUGUAUUUUAGUAAGGUUUUUUUGUUGAUUUAUUUGUUUCCCUUUCUUUCUUCUCAAGAUAGUAAAGGAUUUUUAUUUCUUAAUUUGUUACUGUCCAUGGACAGUCAAAUAACUGCUCACCCUUACUGUAUUAUUUUCCCCUUAGAAAGAAAAGCCUUCCAUCCUACCAUGAAGGAAUUUUUCCUCCAAAAAAUCUUAUCUUCCAUUUCAAAUAGCACUCAUGAGCUUUUAAGAGAGAAAUUCUCUCUUUACUUUGAGGAUAGAACAGUUAAAACAAAAACCUGUUCCUUGAGAAAGAAACCGUAUUUACCUAAACUAACAGGUCUGGGGCCAAAGAAUAGAUUUUUUUAUUGAUUGCAGAUGAAGACCAUGCAUUUUGUACUACAAAUCCUUAUUGCCUCCUCAAAUCCUUUUUGGAAUAAGGCUGGGAAUAAAUUAGUUUAAUUAAAUUCUUUGGGUAUUUCUAAUUAAUAUCUACUGCAAGAUACCCAGGAAAGAAAAGGAAGGGGUGCUGCCGAAAUGCCAAAAUCAAUUGAUCUGUUGAUUUUUAUCAUUGUAGUUGUUGCUUUUCUAGCCAUUUCAAGACUGUAUGUGUUCAUGAAGUCUUAAGUAGAGAAACACCUGUUUCCCCAUUGCUUCUCUCUCCUUCCCCACACCCCUGCACCUGCCCCAACCCCAGGCACUAGAGGGAACAGUAACAGAGGGAGAUUGGCACUGCAUUGCCAGUACUUCACCCAUCUAUACCCCUCCACCACAAAAGAAGGAAAAAACAAAUUAGAAACUAUUUUUUUAAAAAAGGAAAUUGUAGUACUUCAUUUGAAAGCAUACUGUUUUCAACUCAACUCGAUUAACAGAUAGCCUGACAACGUUUUUGUAACCUUUCUUUUGUGCUAUAAUUGACAUUCUUGGCUCAAUCUUUAAAAUAAUUGCAAUUUCAAUUAAGUGAACAGAGAAAAACAAAGAGAGGGAACAGGACAAUGUGAUGGGACCAAAUUUGAUACAGGUCUGGAUUCCUAAAGCCAGUUGUCAAGGUUACCGGAGAAAGUUAGCACUACUCACCCCUUGUUGUUCUUGCCUAUCUCUCAUUAUUACAAUUCAAAGAAUUAGUAAGUUAACUAUACUUCUUUGUGAUUAAAGAUUUCUCUUCAUGCUGCCAAACACUUCUAGAGAAAUUGUAGAAACUCCUGACUUCUAUACCUAAUGUGCUAUCCGGGCCCGAGAGGAGUGUACAGAGAGAUCACUGAAAAUAAAAUAAUAGUUCAAAUUUGAGAUAAGAUUUUCCUGUAGUUCAAAGUGCUUUAUGCAUGUUCACAACUAGGGGAAUCUUUGAAAACAAAGGCUAGUUACUCUGCUCUUGCUCUCCUUGGGACAAACUUUAAUUUGGAACCAGCUGUAGAUUUACAGGAGAAAAUUCUCAAAGGUAUUUUCAGCUGCUAAACUUCUUCUUUAGGCCCGUUGAUUUGAACCUCAGUUUUCCUGAGGAGCCUAUUGAGAUAUAAAUUAAGGGUAAUUUGCAUAUAUCUAAUUAAAAUUGUUCCUACACUAUUGUUGAAAGAAUUAUGGUUUUCAGAGUAGAUGAAAGCAGGGUGUCUUAGUAAUCUUCAUCAUGGCAAACAAAGGUGAGAAGCUGAUAUGAUAGAGAAAAUCUAUGGUAACUUGAUAUUUUAAGGUAAUUUGAGUGUGCUGACCCCACUAUGCUUAAUUCCUUUCCCACAAUCUAUUUUAAACUACACUUUGAUUCUCUUGAGACUUACAGCAUGCAUGUGUGGGUAUGAGCAGACAAGCAGACUUACCUUUGGAGGGUGAAGACCCAGACAAACUGAAGAAACGGAUUCCUGAGGAUGAUCAAAUACAAAUCAUUUUUCCAGAAUCACUCAAUAUUGCCACAUCCCAAACUAAUUCUAGACUAAUCUUUAGAAAGAAGUAAGCUCCUUAAGAAAUCCUACUAUGAAUGUUUUUUCUUCUUAUGGAAUAACACAAGAAGAGGUACAAUGCAGACUCUUAAUUUUGCUGUAAUAAUUCACUUUUGUAUUUAAUAAUUGUACUUCUGUGUGAGUGUGUCACUGAGCUAUUUGUACCAAUUUUCAAUUGAUCAUUCUGAGAGGGGCCUUGAGAAUUUCUGUGUAUGUGUAUGUAUAUCUGUAUUUAUGUGUAGUCAGAAAAAAAAAAGAAUAGGAGACUAAUGAGGUGAGGGAAAAAGUGAUCAAUGUAGAAAAGUGAGUGCUCCUAGUGUACCUAUUUAUGUUAUGUUAGGUGGCUGCUGCCUGUAGCCCUUGAGGAAUAGCUGAUUGCACUAUUCAAAAAUAAAAGCCCAGCACUGUUAAAUUUAGGACCGUGUUUCAAGAAACAGGAAAGCUUUAUCUUUUUCUGAACCCAUUCCCCUUAGCAUUAGAGCCAUCUGACAUGAUGAAAACUAUUAAGUAAAAACCACUACUGACCUUUACAUUAAAUAGCUGUUUUCCUCUUCUAAAUAAUACCCUUGAUUUUAACUAGACUACUUCCUUUUAUUUUCUGCCUAUUGGCUUAAUGUUUUACAGAAAAUACAUAGGUGCAUGCUAGUUUCUCUACUUUGAGCUGAAACAAACAGGAGCAACAAAAGAGAUGACUCACAUAAGUGUGAGAUAGACUGAAUUUCCCACCUUCGUAGCACUGGUAACCUUUGUAAGAGCUGUUUAGAGUUGAGCUUUGGGUUAUAAUAGGGCUUUUUUUUGCACUAAAUAUGACUGCACUGCAUUGCACUACUGAAAUGUACUUACUUGUGCUGGGAGAGAGUGUGUUACGUAUGGGAAAGAAAAAGGCAAAUUAUGGAAGUAGGAGCAUCACUAAAAUGCAGAGUUAUUUUCAUCAUGCUUGAUCUUAGCAGGGUUGGCGAGAAUCUGUGGAAUCUCUGUCAACUCUUGAUCAGGCCUAGGAACCACCAUGCUGAUAGGAUCUGUUUUCUUACUGUAAAGAAGCUGAGUUAGUACAGCAAUUAAGAACAUUUAAGAAAAAGUUUACCCAAUCUUGUUUCUGACUGAGCUCUCAGUAAGAGUUUUAACAGUGAAGAAGCCAAUUGAUAUGAUGUAGAAGUCUUUGCCUUGGCCUCCUCCACAAAGCCCCUUGCUUGUGCACAUUUUAGUGUGGCAGAGGGCAGUAGGAUGUGCUCCUUUCAAAAACACAUAGCCUUGUCCAUAUUGGAAUUACUUUUCAGCCUGAUUAUGCUUCUCCAUCCCUGGGUGAAACCUAGAUCAGGCUAACCAAAGAGGAAGGCUAUGCAUGUGGUAAAGUCCUUUAAGAUGACAGAUAGGGAACAGUGCAAUAAACACUGAAAACCAGUGAAGUGAAAGGUUUAUUUUGAAACAAGCUAGGCCAACUUGGACAUUGGAGGAUGGAUUAGAACAUACUAGCUGCUCCAUCAUAGACUAUCCUUACUAAGCAGAAGACCUUAAUAGUGCCUAAAAGUUUAGUUUUGAAAUUGGUUUUUUCCUAACUUUUCUUUGUUAAAUUUAUUUUUAUUAUCUUUUUUAAUCUUAGAAGUAAUCAGAGUUUGACAGCUCUUUAGUAACUGUUAAUAAAAGAAUCUUUCAUCACAGGAUAAGCAAUAGAUUGUGUGGGAAAUAAUAACACAAGAGUAAAGAUGCUGAAGGACUCUUCUGGAACUCAAAGUGACAGUUUUGAAGGUUCUGGCACAGUAGGAAAGGAUCACAACCCAUAUAAAUGGCUAAUGUUGAAUUUCUCUGAACACUGUCACAUAUGGGGCAUCAAUUUGGAAAAUUCUCAAUUGAGGCCCCUUCCCUAAGAUUACAACAUUGAUAACCUGUCUUUUUCUCUCUCUUCUUUACUAUCCGUCCAAGUCUACUAUUCCAAGUUUAAAUAUUGUUCAGAAAGUUGUCAGCCUUGUUAGUCAGAAAAACUCCAUUUAGAGCCAUCCAAACUAGCAUAAGAAAUUCCUUAAGCACUCAAAGCAUUAUCUCUGUUUUAAGUAAGAAACUAAAUCCAGAGCUUUUAACAGGUACUUAGAAAUAAGUAUUGGGUAAUCACUAAGAGGACAUUGACUGCACCAAACCAAAGCUAUAGAAAGAAAUGAUUGACUUUUUAAAAUAUAUUCACAUUAACUGUCCUAGGAUACUUCUCUUGAGGCUUUGGAAAACUUCUUCCUUGAAAUUUGCAUAUCCACUCCAGUUCUGUCACCAAAGAUUUUAAUCUUCAGAUCGCAAUUUCCUCUCUCCCAGAAAAAAGUACUACAACAGGCUCAAGGGAUAUGCUUUGGUGGUCAAGGGAUUACACUAUGGUUUUCCUUCUGUUCACAAUGGUAUUUACAGGAGACCUUGUCAUCAGAGGACGUACUGAACUAUCUUUAUGACUUUGGAUUUGAUCAGAGGUUUAAAAAAUAGAAAAAAAUAAACAACACUACUUGACACUGUAAAUGAUCUUUAAUAGAGUCAUGACCUGGAGACUGAUGGAGAGAAAGAAACUUCCAUGGAAGAGAGUGAGCUAAAUCAUUUAGAACCAAACAAAGGUCACUGGUGAAACAUAGGGCAGCAUGUACACAGUGCAGAUCAGGGUUCUGUAUGGCCAGAGCCAACAGCAGUGACCGGUGGGAGAGUCAGACAACUGGCCAAUGAAUUCAAGUGUUGAAAAAGCCACAGUCUGGAUUUUGUUGUGAUUUCUGGAGUGGUUGAAACGCCCAUGCCCAUGGCAAGGAAAAUGCUUGGAGGCUGAUCUGUUGUGAUAGUGCCUUUCUUGUCGUAGUGAGUACUAGAUUAAUAAUUUAUUCAGUUACGCUUUUCUGUACCAUUGCCUCCAGUCUUCUGAGGAGGUUUGAAGGGACAGUAUCCACUUAGGAUGAAGGGACAGGAUAUUGCUCUGGAAUGCUGUGAUUUGAUGAUAUUUGCACUAGAUUCUAAACUCUCCUUUAAACUGGAGCAACUGACUGAGAGAAAAACCAAGGACAGCUCAAAGUUAAAAGAAACCAAAAGCAGUAUUUUCUGACAGAUACCAUUUCUUUUUCUCCUUCUUUUUUUCCUGGAAGAAAACUUCACACUAGUUGGCUACCGAGCUCAACUCUUACCAGUUCUUUCUCUUUAUUUUUUGUUUCCAUAUGGAACCAUCUGUGUGAAUUAGUCAUCAGUUAGGUAUAGUUAACGUAAAGAGCCCCUGCCAUUGAAACUUUGCACACCUUCUCUGCUUUAUUGAAGGCAAGGGCCAGUGGGCAGUGAUAGCAGGGGAGGGACCCUCCAGAACCACCCAGCCCUCCAGGAGGCCAAUAAGCAUGGAUAUCAUGUCAGGAGCUGAGCUGACAUAUAUUUACUCAGAGGACAUUGGGGUCUGUAGCUAAUCCUAAAGAAUGCUCCGCAACAGAAGGAAACCAAUGCAUUGUAGAAAACAAAGGGAGAUGGUGCCCGAAGUCUGCCUGUUUCUCUUCUCUUUUCUUUCCCAUCUCACCACCAUGUCCUCUCUAACAGAAUUAUAUUUCAUCUCAUAUAUUAUAUGUUACUAGAAAAGUCAUUUGGUUCCUUGGUUUCUCUCUUUAUCAGUGGGCUGGAAAUUCCUCCAAAUUAAAUAUAAAUACCAGUAGCAGCUCCCCUGUGUCCAGCCAGUUUCUCAAAUGCUGUCCACCUGGUCUUACUGUCCACCUAACAUAACUUGGAGGCUUUGGCUGGCUCAACCACCUGUUCACUUUAUUUUGUUUUCAUUUCCAUUUGAACUUGAAGUGAGGCUAUGGAAAGGUGGAAAUCAUGGGCAAGGUUUGGAGGCUGCAAUUCUAGGGCAUAGCUUGUCAGGAGUUUAUAUUAUCUAAAAUAUAUCUUUCUAUACCCCUUUUCAUUUUAAUCUGUUGCCCUGAUUAUAAUUUCUUUAUAUUUGUGGUUAUUUUUAUAAGAAUAGAGUCCAUUUGCUAUGUCUAUUUGAGUACUUUUUUUCUAUUGUCCCCACAUGGAUGCAGUACCAACCUGUUAAUGAAAUAUCUUUUUAUUAUAUUAUUAAUAUGUAAUUCUACUGUAGACCAAAAAUAUAAAAACAAAUUUGUUCAUUUUAAAGAUAUAAAGAACUAGGGAGUAAAAGAUUAAAAGUUGAAGGAAAAGACAGAAGAGCAGUGGUUAACUAUGUUGAGUUAGAAAUCUAAGAGUAGCCUUACCUGUUUUUUAACCAGUGCUUGCCAAUCAUACCAUAGUUGGAAUUAUGUAAUCUUGGCUCCUUCAUACUUAUGUUCUAUAAUUCUUGUUUGUCUAUUUGUUUUCUUUGAUAUAAUUGAGGUUGCACAUCAUGCUAUUCUUGGCAAUGCCUGAUUCUAUUGUAUUGUACUUUUGUUAGUCAUUUCCUUUAGAAAGAUGGGGGGAAACGUUUAUUUCUUCUUUUAAUUUAAAAUUUGUUUAAUGCACUGGAAAUAAAAUUGGACAUAUUUCACUGUUUAAAAAAUCAGAAACAAAACAAAGCAAAACCAUGAGGGAAAAAAACAGCAAAUAAGCAACAGGGGAAAACAGCUAUGAAAAAAAUAUAUUUGUACUGAAUACACAUACAAACUACAUCCCACAUGAAAGAUUAAUAUCAUCAAGUAAGAAAAAUACAUAGUUUAAACUACAAUGCUGAAAAUAUAAAAGGAACCUGGUAGUUCAAUGGGGAUGGAGAAAACAGAGCAUUCCUCUGAGAGCAGAGAUCUUGUCAUUAUUGCAAUUAAUGCCCAAACAGGUUAAAUGUGGAAGAAAGUAUGGAGGAAAUAACCCCAGCCUUCCUCAUACCACUGGAUUUCCACAUCACCUUUUAACUUAUGCUUGAGCUCCCUUUUGAGAAAAAAUAUUUAAAAACAAAUUGGCUAUGUAACAAAUUUGUGUGUGUGUGUGUAUAUAUAUAUGUAUAUGCUUAUAUAUAUAUAUAUAUGUAUAUGCUUGAGAAAGUGGUUUUUCAAGAUGUAUGUGUACAGUACACACAUGGACACGCUUCAGUCCUCUGACUUCCCAUGUGCUACCUCAUGUGUUUCUCUUCUCAUGAGGAUUUGCAAUGGAUAGUUGUACAACCUGGGGACUGUCAGUGACUCAUUGGUAUCAGCAUAUGCUAAAGAAGCUCUUGAAUCCAAUCUUGAAACCUGAUCUCCCUUCGUCAACAUUCCCCAAUACCAAACUGGCCCGUUUACCCAUACAAAUGCACAGUAAAGGGAAGAACAGCGGUAUUUUUCCUAGCCAACUGACUCUAUCAUUUGUUUAAUGUUUGCUGGUUUUUUUCUGGUUUUGUUUUGUUUUAGAGCAGGGGUGGGAGUGGCUGUAACUUCACAAUCCUAAUACAGUAAAUGUUUUGCAUCUUCCAUGUUUUAUGCAAAAACAGACAUUUAAAUCAAUAAAUAAUUGUGCCCUAGACUGAAGGUUAAUGUUUAGGAGAGGAAAAAAAUUGUUGGAAUUUUUUCUACAUUUUUUUGUGAAGAAUCUUUUUUGGAAAGGAAGGAUACAUAUUUUUGUUGUGUAAUAUUUUCUAUUUUUGAAUGCAUUUUAUUGGUACAAGACUGUUUUUUUGGUGAAGACAUUAUUUAAAAAAAAAAAAAGAAAAAAACUAAUCGAAAAGUUUGCCCUUAAGGAUAUGCUGCAGUUUUGAGGUUAAAAAAAAAUUACUGAUUCAAGAUGCGUGUUAAAAGUUGGGAUUAUAUUGUUGUUUUUUGUAAUUGUUACAAGAAGAAGUUUGUACCCACUGCUGUUUAUUUUGUUUCAGAUGAGUAAGUAAAGGGAUUGUUCUUGUUUUAUUCUUUUUUUAGAGAAAAAAAGCUAUUUAUGAAAUGUCAAAAACACUGGACUGUGAGUUUAAGUGUGGAAGCAUUUUACCACCCUGUGUCUUCAACCAAUUAUGGGAAACCCCUUUUCUCUUCCCCCUACCCCCUGCCUUAGCCUUGCCAAAUGAGAAAAAUAUAACAGCUGUCAGAUUAUCAAAGCCACCGAAGCCCUGCUUUAAUUUUUAUGGUUUGAAAAAGUUGGAAAACCAAAGUUAAAUUUGUUUCUGAAAUCCUGCUGUGCGUUGCCCUUUUUUGUAUGACACAGCCGGGCUCUGCCUCUCUAUCUCAAAUCAUUGCCUUCUUAGGGACUGGGGGCCAACCUGAUGCAAAGAGAGGCAUAAAGGUGGUGAGCCUGAGAGUUGAGGUCUCACGAAGUAAAAUGUGAGUGGGACUUCACCCUCUCAGUGGGCAACCACACUUUCCCAUCCUGAGAUGAGGCUGCCAAGAGAGCACACUGCUAACACUGCCUGAGGAGAGCACGCCUCCUGUCUCCUUCACCCUCUGCUUCUGAGACCCUCCUGUUACUGUUAUCAUCGUUCCCUAGCCUGGCUCUGCCUUUCUCAGCAGCCCACAUUCCAUGGAUGGGAGCAGGGGGGCAGGGACCCAAAGGAGGGAAAUGGCUGUGGGUGGUGUGAAGGCCCCCCAGCCCUCAGGAAGGUGGGGCAAGAGACCACUGAGCACAAGGGAUCUUGCCCACCUCCUCUUUGACUCUGUGGAUUAUCCAUCCAUCUGCUCACUGUGAAGAUGGAGAGGCAGUGCCCUAAGGCUGUUCAAUAGCUUUUCCAUAUUUUUUCAACAUUGAAAAAAUAAUUUUUAAAAACUGUGAUUUUUUUAAAAAAUCAUUUGGCUGGAGGGAAGGGAAAAGGGAAACACCAAAAGCUGUACCAUGAUGAACUGGAGAUAUUUAACUGGGGCACUUUCCAGACCAAGACAAACAAAUUCCUUUCUGGACUCUAAAGCAGCCGAAUCUUGAGACUGUCAAUGACAGAAAGCUGAAGAGAGGCCUCUAUUUCUUCCUUUUUCCUUUCUUCUGUCUAAAAACUCUCUCUUGUUCCCCUUUUCCAGCUUCCCUUGGACUACUGCCCCAAUGGCCCCUUGGACUCGCGUUUCAUGUAUGCGAGCACACACACACACAAACUUGCAAAAUACCGUUUUUCUUAAGGAUUGUGGGACCGAAUAAUAUCACGUGCCUUCAUCUUUUCCUUUUAUAGUUAGAUGAACCUCUUCCUCUUUACAAUUUUUUUAAAAAGUGAUAGGGGAGGUUGAUGUGUUAGUGGAAGAUUUGGGCAUCGUUUGAGAAGUAACUUUUGUUUAACACAUUCCCCCUAAACAUUGAACACAAACAUUUCAACCCCUUCAUGACACUCUUUGGACAUUUAAAGCAUUGAGUAACCAUGUACAUGACAGCCUAAAUCCGUUUGAUUUCAGAGCAUUUCCUGAACAUUGUAUUUCAUAGACUUCUCUGAUUUUUUCAAAAAUGAGGUGAGCAAUGGCAAGCAGCCUUGUUCUCCCAAUUUGGUGCUUUUGCUUUUGGUGUGGGGUGGGCAUGGGGGGUUGGGGGUGGUGUGGGUGUGUUUAGAAAAAAGAUGCAUUCCUGAAGAUCUCUGGUGCUGAAGGGCCUCGAGUUCCUUUCAGAGACUGUAUUUGACACACUUUAGGUACACACAAACGAAUGGUAUCACAUGCAAUAUUUUAAUGGAGCAAUGGGAGAGGCUCUUUGAAAUGGGGUUUGCAUCUUUUUGUAACAUUUUGAUUUCUCUGGUGCCUUAUUCCUACUUGAUGCUGGCACUCACAUACCCACAAGAAGCUGACACAGAAGUCAGCCUUAGGCGUGGGGACAUAUGGGUGAUGUUUGAGCAUGCAGGGGCCAUGGGGAGUUUGGUGUCAGUUGGUGGAGAAGGGACUAGAUGGCAUCUCUUAGCCGAGGCCAACAGGAACUGCACAAGUCCAUUAUAGUCAAAGUUAGCAAUUUUGAUACGUAAACACAAUACUUCAUUCUUCCUCAUCUGAGCUUUCCUUCCUUCUUCCUUUUCUAUCUCUACCUUCUCAUAAAGGUGCUGCUGCUGCUGCUAAGGUGCCCGGAGUCCAGAAUGUCCAUUAAUCACUCAGGCACGAGCCUGGCACUGCCACGUCAGCCCCCAGCAUGACCAAACCCAGGUUUCUCUUGCUUGGGGCUGAGAACUGUCAGAUUUUUCUCAUCAAAAAUGUUUUCCAAGGAAUCAGUGGAUUACAGUUUUUCUGCAUUGAAAAUGCACUUUAAAAAAUAAAUUAAAGCUCCAGACUGUUUAAAAUAUACAGAGGGAGCAGGGGAAAGUUAAGCAUGUGCUAGUGUCUGAACCCAGUUCAGUUUAUCUCCAGUUGAAACGAUAUACACUAUAUUAUGUAUAAAUGUAUACACACUUCCUAUAUGUAUCCACAUAUAUAUAGUGUAUAUAUUAUACAUGUAUAGGUGUGUAUAUGUGCAUAUAUACACACAUGCACAUAACAAAAUCAGAUGCUCAUUACAAAUCCAGAUGCUCAUUACAAAACCAGAUGCUACACAAACAGCAGCAGAGGAAACAAGGUUGGACUCUUGCAACAGAUCACAAAAAAUAAAAACAGCUACUUGCAGUGACUUUGGUCAUUUCUGUAUGUUCAUAAAGAAUGGAUUGUAACAAGGAAAAAAAGGAACAGUGUUAGUGAAAAAGGAAAAAUGGGCGAAACCAUCUUGAUCCGAUGCGAAUGCAGUAAUGUUCUAUAUACCAUUUCAUCAGUUAUUUCUUUUAGUCAUGUUGAUUUGAUUUCAGUUUCUGGCUAUGAAAAACAUUUUUAAACUCGUCACCCACAACAAACUGAACAAAACUACUACAGUGAAAGCCCUUUUCAGUGAAAGAUGUCAGAAACCUCAAAACCUUUGGCCUGACUCAGAACUACCAUGUGAAAAUCAGUACUCUCUUAAUGUUUGAAAUAAAAACUGAAAAAAAAAACAAAAAAACAAAAAACCUUUUUUGAAGCACCUUAACGUGGCCAUCCAUUUGAGAAGUGGGUGCCACUUUUUUCUUUGAGCACCUUAUUGAUGUGUUUGCUAUCUGCUGUCUUUCUGUUACCUGUUGGCUGAAUGGCUAGCUGUUAACAUAUACAUGUGCACAGAAGAGAUAUCUGGGCAUGUAUGUUCUCAAUGAAGUUUACUGUGGUGACUGCUGAAAGGUGAACCCAUUUCCUGAUUUUCCCGCCGCAGUGUUGUGAUAAGAUUCGAAGAAACCUUUUUCCCUGCACAGAAAUGUUUCUUAUCACAUUGUAUCUUAGUAUGGAAAGGAAUAUGGUCCCUUUUUUGCAAUUGCUACUGUGUACACACACACACACACACACACACACACACACACACACUGUAUGUUUAGACCUAAAAUACACACACCCACGCACACACUGUAUGUUUAUGUGACCUAAAACAUACACACAUGCACACACACAUACAUAUCCAUUCAUUCAUUCAUUCAAGUGGUGUUUCCAGUGUCUGUGUGUCACUGUUUAUGCAGUUUCCAUUUCCCAGUGAAUUAUGAGUGGAGGGCAACUUUUCUAACCAGAUUGUCUUUUCAGAACAAAGACCUGGGAAUUGAGGAAGAGUUUGGAAAGAGGGAGAGGCAAGGAAAGAGAGCUUUAAAUUGAAAGGUUAAUUUCCUAAGAGGAACCUGGGCUGAAUGACUGCAGUGUUAUACCCUCCAAUCUUUGCAGGUGGGCAUGGAACACUGCUUGUAUCACUCUGUGCACGGUAUAAAUCCAUAUAUCCACAAAAACACACAUCCAUCCAUCAACAUAUACAUGGUUUGGGAUGAGCAGGUCAAUAGUUUUGAGAGGGAGUUUGUUCCUUUUUUUUUCUCAUUAUACUCUUAAAUUGUUGUCAGUUAUCAAACAAACAAACAGAAAAAUUGUUUGGAAAAACCUUGCAUACGCCUUUUCUAUCAAGUGCUUUAAAAUAUAGACUAAAUACACACAUCCUGCCAGUUUUUUCUUACAGUGACAGUAUCCUUACCUGCCAUUUAAUAUUAGCCUCGUAUUUUUCUCACGUAUAUUUACCUGUGACUUGUAUUUGUUAUUUAAACAGGAAAAAAAACAUUCAAAAAAAGAAAAAUUAACUGUAGCGCUUCAUUAUACUAUUAUAUUAUUAUUAUUAUUGUGACAUUUUGGAAUACUGUGAAGUUUUAUCUCUUGCAUAUACUUUAUACGGAAGUAUUACGCCUUAAAAAUACGAAAAUAAAUUUUACAAGGUUUCUGUUUUGUGUGGAAGAGUAAUUGAUGUUGCUAAGAAUGAUGUUUGUUUUUUUGGGGUUUUUGUUGUUUUUUUUUUAAAUGUUACCAGCACUUUUUUUGUAAGUUUCACUUUCCGAGGUAUUGUACAAGUUCACACUGUUUGUGAAGUUUGAAUAUGAAGGAAUAAUUAAAAAAAAAAAAACUCUUC